ACUGUGUGGGCUGAGGAUGCACCCCCACUCGGGGCUGGGGGCUCCUGGCCUGCUCCCACAGACAGGGGCAGGCGGGGCCUCUGUGGCAGUGACCCCUAACCUCUCCAGGACACAAAAACAGGUGGCCCGAGUCCGGGAGGACACAGCCACAGCCCUCCAACGGCUGGUGGAGCUGACGACCAGCAGGGUGACCCCGGUGAGGAGCCUUCGGGACCAGUACCACCUCAUCCGGAAGCUGGGCUCCGGCUCCUACGGCCGCGUGCUCCUUGCCCAGCCUCACCAGGGGGGUCCAGCUGUGGCUCUGAAGCUCCUGCGUCGGGAUUUGGUCCUGAGAAGCACCUUCCUGAGGGAGUUCUGUGUGGGCCGCUGCGUCUCUGCACACCCAGGCCUGCUGCAGACCCUGGCAGGACCCCUACAGACCCCCCGCUAUUUUGCCUUCGCCCAGGAGUACGCGCCCUGUGGGGACCUCAGCGGGAUGCUGCAGGAAAGGGGCCUCCCAGAACUGCUGGUGAAGCGGGUGGUGGCCCAGUUGGCAGGAGCUCUGGACUUCCUCCACAGCCGGGGGCUGGUCCACGCAGAUGUCAAACCUGACAACGUGCUGGUCUUCGACCCGGUCUGCAGCCGUGUGGCCCUGGGAGACCUGGGUCUGACCCGGCCAGAGGGCAGCCCGACCCCCGCCCCACCAGUGCCUCUGCCCACGGCACCGCCUGAGCUCUGUCUCCUGCUACCGCCCGACACCCUGCCUCUGCGGCCAGCCGUGGACUCCUGGGGCCUGGGGGUGCUUCUCUUCUGUGCUGCCACUGCCUGUUUCCCUUGGGACGUGGCACUGGCCCCCAACCCUGAGUUCGAGGCCUUCGCUGGCUGGGUGACCACCAAGCCUCAGCCACCUCAGCCACCACCACCCUGGGACCAGUUUGCGCCCCCAGCCCUGGCCUUGCUCCAGGGGCUUCUGGACCUGGAUCCCGAGACUAGGAGCCCCCCACUGGCUGUCCUGGACUUCCUGGGGGACGACUGGGGGUUGCAAGGGAACAGAGAGGGACCUGGGGUUUUGGGGAGCGCCGUGUCCUAUGAGGACAGGGAGGAGGGAGGCUCAAGCCUGGAGGAGUGGACAGAUGAGGGUGAUGACAGCAAAAGUGGUGGGAGGACGGGGACAGAUGGGGGAGCUCCCUGACCAGGUGACAGAGACAGGUGGCCAGAGCCUGGGCCAGAGGCCCUUCCCCCAGCCCCCAGGGCCACCUGGAUGGAGAGACAGCUGCACCCGGGAGGACAGAGAGGGAACACAUUGCACUCUCCCUACGGAACGCUGGGCUUGGACGCGCAUUCCUCUUCCAACUGAGGACCCAAGAGCCCAGCUCCUGCCC